CUUCCUCCUACCUAGAGAUGGGAAAAGGGGCAUUCCUUCUUUCCUCCUUGGCCGUGGAACAUUGUGGCCCUUUCCUCUGGUUGCCACCUGCAGCAGAGUGGGCAGAACAAGGGACAGGCUCAGGAGGGGCUCCGGCAGGCCUGGGAGCCCCCUCAGUCUUACUUAUCUCCCACACCCUGGCUGCAAAAGGCCUCCAUUGAGUUGGCUCUGCACUGGGCUGCUGCCCCCGCAGGUCAGGGCCUCGGGGCCUCCUUAGGGGACGAAACGACAAAGUUGGAAGGAGCUACCACUUUUCCUGUUUUCCCCCCACCCAACCCCAACUCUGCGGGGUGGAGGAGACUAGAGGAGAGGGGAAAAGUGUCUUUCUGUUAGGAGAAAACCAAGUCCGAGGUGAGAGGUCGGAGGGGAAAGAAAAAAAGGAAGCUGUCCCUCUGCGCCUCCUCCCGCGGUGUCCCUGCUAUGGUGCGCGCCAAGGUCUCCCGCUCCCAGGCUGGAGCGGCCAAGAUAACUGUGGUCUCACUCCCCCAGGUGCAGGCUUCCAGCCGCAGCUUCUUUUCCUCUUCUCCGCUCUCACCCUGCAGGGGGCUCCCCAGAUCCGCACAAGGAGACCGUUAUUCUCAGCGUUGUAAGGAGCGGGUGAACGCUUUGGCCAUUGCCGUGAUGAACAUGUGGCCCGGAGUGCGCCUACGAGUGACUGAGGGCUGGGACGAGGACGGCCACCACGCUCAGGAUUCACUCCACUACGAAGGCCGUGCUUUGGACAUCACUACGUCUGACCGCGACCGCAACAAGUAUGGGUUGCUGGCGCGCCUCGCAGUGGAAGCCGGCUUCGACUGGGUCUACUACGAGUCCCGCAACCACGUCCACGUGUCGGUCAAAGCUGAUAACUCACUGGCGGUCCGGGCGGGCGGCUGCUUUCCGGGAAAUGCAACUGUGCGCCUGUGGAGCGGCGAGCGGAAAGGGCUGCGGGAACUGCACCGCGGAGACUGGGUUUUGGCGGCCGAUGCGUCAGGCCGGGUGGUGCCCACGCCGGUGCUGCUCUUCCUGGACCGGGACUUGCAGCGCCGGGCUUCAUUUGUGGCUGUGGAGACCGAGUGGCCUCCACGCAAACUGUUGCUCACGCCCUGGCACCUGGUGUUUGCCGCUCGAGGGCCGGCGCCCGCGCCAGGCGACUUUGCACCGGUGUUCGCGCGCCGGCUACGCGCUGGGGACUCGGUGCUGGCGCCCGGCGGGGAUGCGCUUCGGCCAGCGCGCGUGGCCCGUGUGGCGCGGGAGGAAGCCGUGGGCGUGUUCGCGCCGCUCACCGCGCACGGGACGCUGCUGGUGAACGAUGUCCUGGCCUCUUGCUACGCGGUUCUGGAGAGUCACCAGUGGGCGCACCGCGCUUUUGCCCCCUUGAGACUGCUGCACGCGCUAGGGGCGCUGCUCCCCGGCGGGGCCGUCCAGCCGACUGGCAUGCAUUGGUACUCUCGGCUCCUCUACCGCUUAGCGGAGGAGCUACUGGGCUGAGCGUCCCAGGCAUAGAAACCUCGAAGCGCCCGAGGAAACGAGGGCCUGCUGGCUGAGAUAUGGGGCUGUGGGCAGCAGACGAUGCCGACUGGAAGGGAGGGAGAGGGAGGGGGAGGGAGAAAAUGGGGCUAUGCCUGGCUUAGGGGCAACCUCGUACUGAGAGGAGGUGAUACCGGGUCCUAGGUAGGUAGGGCUGAUGGUGCGCACUCCUUAAAGAGGACUAUUUAGCCUCUCCCCCAGUGCUUCAGCCCCACCCGAUAAUUUUAUUUUAUUUCUUAUUUAUAAAUUGUAAUAUAAUGAUUCCCUUGCCCAGCUUGCCAAGGUGAGGGGCUGGGGCAUGGCAUUAACACUGUCUGACACAGCCAGCCAGUCUGACAUCUGACGUUUUCCUGCAAGGUGGGCUAAUAAAGGGAAGGCUUUCAGGAGCUUACUGGAAAACACUUCCAUUCAGAGGGUGAUUCACCUCCAGAGAGGGGGAUAAAGGUGGCCAACCUGAGUUAACAGCUUACUUCCGGCUCCCCCUCCUUCCUCAGCAGGGUCUUUGGGACCCUUUUCCUCCCUUCAGAAGGGGCAUCCCAACCCAUAAGCAACAGAGCCCACAAGAGUCGUACCCUUUUCCAGGCUGCUGUUUCCGUCUCCCAUCCAGAGAGGACCAGCAUUUCGCUCCUGCGGCUGAAGGGUCCAGGGUUGUCCCAGGUGGGAAAGACUGUGCACACCUCUUCUCUGUUUAUAGGGGCUCCAGCAGGGGCUCAGGCCCCUAUGAGUACUGAUACUCAAAGCAUCUAGUCCCCUAUUGUUAGCCAGUAGUCCUGGUCCCCAUCCUACCUUGGUGGCAGGGCCUGGAUGGGGUGGAUGUUUUUUCUGAUAUGCCACUGGGCCAACUGAUGAUCCAUGGGAAACCUGGGUAAUAAUUUGCAAUCGUCGCAUAGUCAUGGCCUGAAAAAGGAAGGGGGGCACAGUAAGAGGCUGGAAUAUUUCCUUACUGAAGGGCUGCUCAGAGAGAGAGAAUGGAUUCAGCCUGGGUGUAUGUGGGGGAAGUAGAUUCCCUAAACAAGGGCAUAUCAGCAUUACAACCCGAGCUCCCCUCCUGAUCGCUGGCCCUGAUUGUUGUUUCUACUGGCUUGGUCUUCAGCGCCUCCUCCUCCCUCUCCCAUUAUCACCAGCUCUACUUCCCUAGCCUGGGUGUUUUUGGAACCUUUAGGUUCCAACGCAGUAGACACCUGGAAUCCAGGCAGGCAGGUGCCCCUGAGUUAGGAAUGGAAGCUCUGGAGGAAGCUGGGCUGCUCCAGAAGGGAAGUGUCUUGGGUGGAGGUGAGGCGGGGAGGAGGAAAUAGUCGGGGGUUGUUGGUACCACCCGGAGCUCGCCCUUGCCAGUAGCCGCUGUGCGCUCCCAUCGCACAGGGUCCCUGCUAUACACCGCCCUCUGGUGGCCUUCAAGAGAAUUCUAGGCCUAUGCAUAUGGUUCUCUGAAACGGAAGGCAAGCGGUCUCAGACAUGGAAGGGUGUACUGGACCUGCGCAAAGGAGCCCGCUCCCAGGAGGGAGAGAUGAUGGGUGGGCCUUGUUAAGCUGCCAGCGCUGAGUCACACAUAUCAGGAGCUGUCAAGGAGUCCACCUGCUUCUCCUUGGGCAAGUCGUUCCAAACCAUGGCACUUUUACAUCACUCCUGCCUAGUUUAGCUCUGUGGUUCCUGGAAGCUGCAGAUGCCCUACUAGUAUACCUGUAGUAGCCCAGACUUCCUUAUGUAUCAAAGUUGCCGCCUCAUGUCCCUCACCCUCAUGACCCUUGAGUUCAAUUGUCAAGGAGGUGAAAGCAUAAUAGGGUUCCAGGUAGUGCUUGAUAAAGGCAAUAUUUGGAAGCAGGUCAAGUUUACCUUUGGUGUCCUUCCACCCACUGCUGCCCUCAACCCACACUGAGGCUCUGUUGCCACCUUUGUUUUUCCGGGUCUCAGAAACACAUCCCAAGCUGUGGACCUUUCCUACUUUCUAAACCUGCCCUUGUCUCUUUUUAUCAGAUCUGGUGCCUUCCUGUCAUGUCACCACAGGUGAUGACUAAUCCGAUAAAUGAAUUAGUUGUCCUAUGUUGAUGGGCUCCUUGGUUUUACUGCCCUUCCCAGGUAAUCAGGUAAUGCAUAUAUAUAUACAUGUAUUUUUUAAAGAGACAGGAUCUCGCUCUGUUGCCCACGCUGGAGUGCAGUGGUGUGACCUUGGUCCCCUGUAGCUUCAACCUCCUGGGCUCAAGCAAUCCUCCCACCUCAGCCUCUCAAGUAGCUGGGACUACAGGUGCAUGCCGCUAUGCCUGGCUAAUGUUUGUAUUUUCUGUAGAGACAGAGUCUUGCUACGUUGCCCAGGCUGGUCUUGAACUCCUGGGCUCCCGCCUUUGCCCCACAAAGUGCUGGAAUUACAGGUGUGAGCCCCUGUGCCCAGCAGUAAUACAUAUAUCUUACAGUUUUAACCUUUAACCAUAAAAUCAUAAUGGUGAUGAUUCCUAGCACUGUAAUAAGUUAGCUAGGGAGAUAUUUCAGGACAAGGAGAACUCAUUGGUUUCCCUUAAACUACAUCCUGUAAGUAACUUUCUAGGCUUGAGGCUUACCUCUCAACCCUCACUUCCUCCCUUUAUUAUCUUUAUUCCUUUGAGGCCCCUCCUAACUCUCAAAAAAAAAAAAAAUCCAUGACUUGCCUUCAAGCGGCAAUGCGCACCAUCUUGGUGCAGCAGGUGGGCAUAUUCACUUGGCCAUGCAACACCUCCCAAUUGCAGCACCUUUCACCAUCAACAAAAUAGGCGAUGAUGAUUUGGCUUAGAAGCCAGCUAGAUCUGGGGAUAAUGAUACCUCCGUGACAGGAUGGUUGAGAAGGAUUGUGCUGGAUGUGGAGUAGGCGCUCAGUAAAUGUUUUCUAUUCUUUGGCCACUUCUGACUGACUUUGCUGCCUUCCGAUCACUUCUUUCCUCACCACUCCACUAAAAGCAUCAGUCGUGCAAACUUUCUGGGGUUUUGUCACAGCACUUUCAGAAGCUGGAGGUAUACUAGCAGCAUUUCUGUAGUAGUCCAGACUUCCUUACAUAUAGAAGUUGACUCUUCAUGUCCCUCACCUUUGUGACCCUUGAGCUCAGUAGUCAAGGAGGUGAAAGCAUAAUGGGGUUCCAGGUAGUGCCUGAAACUACUUUUCUGAAGAAGUAUAAUUAAAAGUAAUCUUGUUUUGAGAA